AGUGUCAGCCCGAAGGCUGAAGGAAAAAGAGCAACAGAUCCAGGGAGCAUUCACCUGCCCUGUCUCCAAACAGAGGCGAUUGCAGGGAGGUGGCUGACCGUUGAUCACACCCAGAGCUGGUUAUGGGAAUUUACUCCAUGGAAAGACUGCAAAACUGCCUGAAAUGUGUUUUGGCAUCAGCUACUGACACCCUUGUGCCUCACCUACCCCCAACCUCCCAGAGGGAGCAGCUAUUUAAGGGGAGCAGGAGUGCAGAACAAACAAGACGGCCUGGGGAUACAACUCUGGAGUCCUCUGAGAGAGCCACCAAGGAGGAGCAGGGGAGCGACGGCCGGGGCAGAAGUUGAGACCACCCAGCAGAGGAGCUAGGCCAGUCCAUCUGCAUUUGUCACCCAAGAACUCUUACCAUGAAGACCCUCCUACUGUUGGCAGUGAUCAUGAUCUUUGGCCUACUGCAGGCCCAUGGGAAUUUGGUGAAUUUCCACAGAAUGAUCAAGUUGACGACAGGAAAGGAAGCCGCACUCAGUUAUGGCUUCUACGGCUGCCACUGUGGCGUGGGUGGCAGAGGAUCCCCCAAGGAUGCAACGGAUCGCUGCUGUGUCACUCAUGACUGUUGCUACAAACGUCUGGAGAAACGUGGAUGUGGCACCAAAUUUCUGAGCUACAAGUUUAGCAACUCGGGGAGCAGAAUCACCUGUGCAAAACAGGACUCCUGCAGAAGUCAACUGUGUGAGUGUGAUAAGGCUGCUGCCACCUGUUUUGCUAGAAACAAGACGACCUACAAUAAAAAGUACCAGUACUAUUCCAAUAAACACUGCAGAGGGAGCACCCCUCGUUGCUGAGUCCCCUCUUCCCUGGAAACCUUCCACCCAGUGCUGAAUUUCCCUCUCUCAUACCCUCCCUCCCUACCCUAACCAAGUUCCUUGGCCAUGCAGAAAGCAUCCCUCACCCAUCCUAGAGGCCAGGCAGGAGCCCUUCUAUACCCACCCAGAAUGAGACAUCCAGCAGAUUUCCAGCCUUCUACUGCUCUCCUCCACCUCAACUCCGUGCUUAACCAAAGAAGCUGUACUCCGGGGGGUCUCUUCUGAAUAAAGCAAUUAGCAAAUCAUGUA